GCUCAGCAUUUGGGGACGCUCUCAGCUCUCGGCGCACGGCCCAGAGACGCUCUUCUGGCUCUUCCGUGACGCAUUACAACAGCCAUCCAGGCCGGUCCAGUUACGCUGCAUUCCUUCCUCCUUCCCAUUUCGGCGGACCUGCAUCCAGCUAGAGACUAGCAGAUUGAAUCGAUAUUCAUUAAGUUAGGAAUGGUUGGUGGUCCUAAGAGCCUCAGCAACCGAGAGGAGUCUUGUUAUUUAAAAAACAACGAUACUGGGCGUGGUCGUGGGCCUGUAGUCCCAGCUGCUCAAGCUAGUGGAUCUCUUGAGUCCAAGGCCAAUGUGAGCAACAUAGCAAGACCCAGUCUCAAAAAAUAAAUACAUAAUAAUAAUAAAAAACCCUCGUUCACCUAAACAGAUCUAUAAUUUAUAGAAUGUAAAGCAGCAAUAUUCAGGCAAUAUUAAGGAAGAUUUUUGGUAAGACUGGGGCAGCAGAGGUGCCCUUGAUGGGCAAGGGCCAGGAGUGUUAACACAGUCCUGCUUAGUAAUUUCUUCCCUUCUUCCAAGUCUGUCGAUUAUCUAAAGGUCAAGGGUUUGUCCAAAAAUGUCCCUUGCAUCUGCAGUGGAAGGAUGUGACAUGUAUGUGCAUUUUUACAAUUGGAGGUUUGUGAUUUGGAGACCGUUUAGAUUUUGUAAUUUCCCGCAGUGCCAACUAGACUGCCUGUGGUAAAUGCCCAGGAAAUAUUGCUGACUCACUGACUUUGAUUAGGAGCUCAGUCUUGCACUGGAGUCUCAAUAUUUAGCAUCUUGUGUCUUUGAGCUAUUAAACUAUGGUAUUGAUUGACAUUAGGCUCGCAGUCAUGGCCGUUAGUUUCCUGGCUAAUUUCUGAUUUAAGUAGUUUUCCUGGCAAAGUAGAUGUGCUUCUAUAAUUGCUAUUGAUUUUGAGGGCUGUAGGCUCUUCCUACACCACUGGGCCUAGAAUCUGGCACUAAUGCAUUGUCUGGAGCCUUUGUUCUCACCCUUCGCUUGUGCAGAGCCUGGAGCCUGCGGAGACAUUUUUCAUUAAAGGAGAGCGGGAUUGUCACAAAAGGAGUCUCAGGCUCUAGUGGGCUGCUUUAAACAACCAUUUAUUCCACAAAAUAUUAAUUACCUACUGUGUUCCACUCAUAGUUAUGAGCACUAGGGAUACAGCAGUGAACAAAACAGACCCCCGCCAAAAAUAAAAUCCCUGCUCUUUAGACCUUAAAUCUGGCGGAGAGAGAAGGAAAAGAGACAAAAUAAGUGAAUUGUUGGAUUUUAAACUUUAUAUUUUCCCAAAUUAAUACUAGUUUCUAAACUUGGUGGGAGUUCAUUUCCCCUUUAAUCCAGCUGUUCCACAGACCUAAACUUCACAUUUUACCUACCUCGGGGAAGUUUUGCUUAAAAUUAUGGUGUCUUAAGCUGCCUUCCAGAUUCAAUUGUGAGAAUUAAAUAGAAAUGGAAUGUUCCUCUUUUUUUUCACAUGAGAAUCCUCUUCACUUGCCCUGGUGCCACACCCUAUUCUAGUUGUAGGCCACACCAGAGGAAAUUCCAGUCCUUCAAAAAAAUUCUUUCCACCCAUUCACUGCCUGGUAUCUUUUUUCUUCUGCUGUUGCCAGAGGCAGUCCUCAUCUACUUUCUCCAGGGACAGGUCAGCAGUAGGGGUCAGGAGAUGCCCAUAUUUGUCCUUCUGGGUGGUUCUACCAGAUGACUUCCAAAUCUCCCUUCUAGGGUACACCCUGAAGCUGUUUUUUUUUUUCUUUUUUUUUUCUUUUGAGAUGGAGCCUGGCUCUGUCACCCAGCCUGGAGUGUAGUCGCACGAUCUCUCCUCACUGUAGCCUCCGCCUCCCAGGUUCAAGUGAUUCUCCAGCCUCACCCUCCCGAGUAGCUGGGAUUACAGGUGCCUACCACCAUGCCGGGCUAAUCUUUGUAUUUUUAGUAGAGACAGGGUUUCAUCAUGUUGGCCAGGCUGGUCUGGAACUGUUGAGCUCAAGUGAUCCGCCUGUCUCGGCUUCCCAAACUGCUGGGAUUACAGGCGUGAGCCACUAUGCCUGGCCCACCCUGAAGCUUUUAAUCCAGCUGAGCUCAACUGGACAGGCGGCCAGGCCCUGUUGAAAAUACAAUAUGUGGGCCAUAAAACACUGAAAUUGAGUUGCAGACUUGAAGGCCUGGAUUUCCCAACCCUGAAAGUGCUUCAUGCCAAGUGACAUCAUUCUUCCUGCCGGUCUCUUUCCACCCACUCCAACCCCAGAUCAGGAUACCAGCAGAGAGAGGCUGUGAGAGCAUGAAGCUGCAACAAGUCAGUAGGGAGCAAACAAAUAUUGAUUCAGAUCAGGCCACAGAAGAGACAAGCUGGAGCAAGUGCUGUGUGUCCCUCCUGCUCAGUUUGAUCGAGGUCACUGGGCCGAAUUCCAGGAAUUCUGGGGAAUGAGUUGGCCCUGUGACUCAGUCAUUAAUCAAGACCAUAAAACCAAGGAGAAGAAUAUCUGCUUUCAAAAAGGUUCUGAUAAAUAAAGAUGCAGUAGGUGGGUGGAGGAUGGAGUACAGUGGGAACCCCUCUCCUCACCCAGUACAUUUUUUUUUUUUUUUUUUUUUAGUUUAAAAUUCCAGUGUGGCCUGUAGACUGUGUGUCCAGGACUGUGUACAGUAAGAGCUUUGAUGGAGAACCCAACUCUCCACACUCCCACCUCUACCCAUUUUUGCUUUAAAAUCUUCAUUUGAAUCACCAGUCCCUGAUUGAUUCACCAUGGUUGCUAAGAAUCUGUUUUGCGGUAACGCAUCAACACUCCACGUUUAAACUGUGAAGUGGGUGUGUCCACAAAACUUCUGGAUUAGACUCAGAUUUGCCUGUGCAGACCAGCCCUGUUGCAGUAUGUUUUUGUUUGUUCAGAUUAACAUUUGGGCUUUUUGGAACUGGUUCUUAAUUUAGUUCAGUAGAAUGUGUUUUUACUAUUUGAAGUGUUGACUUUUAAGUUUUCUUUUGUUUGUUUGUUUUAACCUUUUUGUAAACUUUUACUCUUCUUUUUGGGAGUAAAGUUAAAACUGCUUCACUUGUCCUUUUUUUGUUUGUAACUGCACUUUCGUAGUGAAGCAAUAGAAUACAAUAAAAUCUAUAGAGUUUUUUUUUUUUUAAUAAGGACAAACCCUUAAAUUAUUAGGUUGGUACAAAAGUUAAUUGUGGUUUUUGCCAUUAAAAGUAAUGGCAGUUAUUUUUGCACCAACCUAAAUAAUAUAGUCCUUAUGUUAAAUGUAAAUGACUUGUUUCUCAAUAACUGCACUGAUUUCAUUAAUGAUCAGCCUUGCACUGUGAGCUUUUUUAGCCAGGCAUUCACAGUCUCAUUUAUCAGCCUUUUCAAGGCAGAAGAAACUGUUCUUUUCAUUAGGGUGGGGCCAAGUGACCUGUUUUCCUACCCAAGUAGUGAAUGAUUUUAAACCAGUUUGAGGUGGGUAUGGCUCUUAUCAGUGAGUCUCCCUGUACCUCUAGUUUAUUUCCUUAAACAGAAAAACGUUCUCUGAUAAAGGGUCAUUUUAAUGAUGUUGUCUAGUGACCCUGCCCUCCCUGGGAAUGGAAGGCACGGCACUGAUGUGUAUGUAGAUGUACUCAUCAACAGAUUGAAUUUGCUGAUUUUUUUUUUUUUUUCUUGUUGGAGAGUUGAAACCAGUCGGCAAGCUGGGUGAGGUUGAAGUGUUGGAAAGAGUGGUGCAAACUGCCAUUUUCAUGUUCUUUAGAGAAGUCUGCCAGAAAAGGAGUAGUGGUUCUGUUUUUAAUGGAUUUAUGAGUUUUAUACGGUGAUGAGGAGUGAGUAGAGGUGAAAUUGUCUCAUACAGCAUGUAGGCUUUAUUUUUUAUUUUCAUUCAAAACAGUAAGUACACUGAAGUCAGAGUAGUUGUUUUCAGUAAGAAAAUUCUGCCUCCAGAGCAAAUGUUUUGGUGAAUAGAUAAAUAUGAGUACUGAGUCCCAAUCAUUUUGGCUCAUAGGUUCCCCAGUAUUUCCAUAGGCAAGCUUAACUUUGCACCAUUCAGAGACUUAUAUUUUAGGUUCCCCACAGGGCACCCCACUGGACGUGGCUCAUUUUCCAGCCUGUAGUCUUGUUCUUCUGCCACCCUGGGGCAUUAUUCCUCUUCCCCUCUCCCCAGGCCUUCCCCCUUGCUUCUUGGCUGGAACCUCCCAUGGUGAUUCACCCUUCUCAGCCUAGGCAGACAGCACCUCCCUGUUAAGCCCUUAACUAAUCCCGCUCUGAUGGCUGUGAUCUUUCUCUCUGUGUCUUAAUCACUUGGAAUAAAGAACCAUUGUGGUGAGGUUGAAAGGGCAUUGGCCCAGGAGUCUGGGGAUCUGGGUUUUGGCCCUGCCUCAGCUACUUAAUUCACUGGGUGACCCUGGACUAGACUCUCAGUGUGUCACAGAGGCACGAAGGGAAGAGAGCUCAAAGGUCCUGCAGGGUGGAAGUCUGCAUUUCACAGUUUUAUAAGUGUCUUUUGUAUCCUUUAAUAUAGUGCAGGCUCAGCGUAUGCUUGGUAUGGGUUCGUUGAUUAAUUCCUUGCGUAUUACCAGUGUUUGUAACCUACAGUAGCACUGCCAAGACUUCCUUUUCCUGCUUUCAAGGAUAGCAGCACACUGACACAUUCUCAUUAGUCAAAUAUGCUAUAUUAAACUAAUGUUUUAACAAACAGUGAAUCGCAAAGCCAACUGUUCCUUCCAGCGAAUAAUAGAUCAUAUGCAAAAUGACUUUGCAUUGCUAGGGGAUUUGAUGGAGUGAAGAAGCAAGCACUGUAUUUUAUUUCUUUUUAUUUUGUUUUGUUUUUUGGACAUAACCUCAAGAUUUUAUUGUCCUCAUAAUAAAACAAAAGAUGAUGCUUAGAACUGGAUCACUUGGCCCUUUCUUUUGUUAUCUCCUCCCAGUUGAAAAUGUUUGCAUGUCUUAACAGCCAGCAUUUUCUUAGAUCUGCAGAUGGGGUCAGCACACUCAAGCCUCAGCACAACCUCCUUUGUAAUUUUACCCGUUUUCCAGAAAAUUGCCUUAGUCUACCCACCAUAGUCACUCUGCUUCUUGUCAUAACGCCGCUUUCCCUGGGCAUACAGGGAGUCCUGGUAUUGUGCCGUUUUGUGGGGUUGGUGCUUGCCACACUUCUUACAGAAAGCCCAGUGGGUUUUAGGAAUGUUCACCAUGUUUUCCGGAAUGCUAUCGGCAUGGGAGGAAAGUGGCCAUAUUUUAUUUCUAGGGUGAAAAUGUUUGCCAUUAAACUCACAUGAAGUAGGAAAUAUUUAUAUGGAUACAAAAGGCACCUGCAUGGGAUAAUGUCAAAUUUCAUAGAUACUGCUUUGUGCUUCCUUCAAAAUGUCUACUGUUCACGAAAUCCUGUGCAAGCUCAGCUUGGAGGGUGAUGUGUGGAUGAGGUCACCAUUGUCAACAUUUUGACCAACCGCAGCAAUGCACAGAGACAGGAUAUUGCCUUCGCCUACCAGAGAAGGACCAAAAAGGAACUUGCAUCAGCACUGAAGUCAGCCUUAUCUGGCCACCUGGAGACGGUGAUUUUGGGCCUAUUGAAGACACCUGCUCAGUAUGACGCUUCUGAGCUAAAAGCUUCCAUGAAGGGGCUGGGAACCGACGAGGACUCUCUCAUUGAGAUCAUCUGCUCCAGAACCAACCAGGAGCUGCAGGAAAUUAACAGAGUCUACAAGGAAAUGUACAAGACUGAUCUGGAGAAGGACAUUAUUUCGGACACAUCUGGUGACUUCCGCAAGCUGAUGGUUGCCCUGGCAAAGGGUAGAAGAGCAGAGGAUGGCUCUGUCAUUGAUUAUGAACUGAUUGACCAAGAUGCUCGGGAUCUCUAUGACGCUGGAGUGAAGAGGAAAGGAACUGAUGUUCCCAAGUGGAUCAGCAUCAUGACCGAGCGGAGCGUGCCCCACCUCCAGAAAGUAUUUGAUAGGUACAAGAGUUACAGCCCUUAUGACAUGUUGGAAAGCAUCAGGAAAGAGGUUAAAGGAGACCUGGAAAAUGCUUUCCUGAACCUGGUUCAGUGCAUUCAGAACAAGCCCCUGUAUUUUGCUGAUCGGCUGUAUGACUCCAUGAAGGGCAAGGGGACGCGAGAUAAGGUCCUGAUCAGAAUCAUGGUCUCCCGCAGUGAAGUGGACAUGUUGAAAAUUAGGUCUGAAUUCAAGAGAAAGUACGGCAAGUCCCUGUACUAUUAUAUCCAGCAAGACACUAAGGGCGACUACCAGAAAGCGCUGCUGUACCUGUGUGGUGGAGAUGACUGAAGCCCGACACGGCCUGAGCGUCCAGAAAUGGUGCUCACCAUGCUUCCAGCUAACAGGUCUAGAAAACCAGCUUGCGAAUAACAGUCCCCGUGGCCAUCCCUGUGAGGGUGACGUUAGCAUUACCCCCAACCUCAUUUUAGUUGCCUAAGCAUUGCCUGGCCUUCCUGUCUAGUCUCUCCUGUAAGCCAAAGAAAUGAACAUUCCAAGGAGUUGGAAGUGAAGUCUAUGAUGUGAAACACUUUGCCUCCUGUGUACUGUGUCAUAAACAGAUGAAUAAACUGAAUUUGUACUUUAGAAACACGUACUUUGUGGCCCUGCUUUCAACUGAAUUGUUUGAAAAUUAAACGUGCUUGGGGUUCAGCUGGUGAGGCUGUCCCUGUAGGAAGAAAGCUCUGGGACUGAGCUGUACAGUAUGGUUGCCCCUAUCCAAGUGUCGCUAUUUAAGUUAAAUUUAAAUGAAAUAAAAUAAAAUAAAAUCA